CUGCUCUCAAACCACCCCACUUCUGUCCCUCAGAGGUGGGACAGUGGGGAGAGGAGGAAGAGGACUCAGAGGCUGGAGAAGGAAGAGAAAAGGCGUUGCUGUGGGAAAGACCUGGCAAGGAAAAGGCAGCGGAACCCCAGAGAGCAGGGUAGACGCCUGCGGCCCAGGAGAACCGAGCAAGGCAAGGAGCUCAAAGGGAGAGCUCUGAGUGUGCAGGGCACCUCUGGCCCUGUGCCGACUCCUCACCUGGGUCUGGCCCUUUACCUGGGAGUCGUUCUCUUAAGCCAGGAGGGCACCACCCAUCUUGAUGGCCCAACUCACUCCAGGAAACACAAUGGGUUUGCUGACCGUGGCGGAUGAGAGUGGCGGCAGGUGCGAGGGGAGAGAACAUUGAGCAUUUGAAGCUUCGACUUGAGGCUCGGCCACCGACUUUGCUUCUCUUCACAGAGCCCUCAGAGCCCCUCCCUGAGGAGUCCAAACCUGUGGAGAUGCCCUUCCACCACUGCCACAGGGACCCCCUUCCGCCGCCGGGCCUUACCCCUGAGAGGCUGCAUGCACGGAGGCAGCUAUAUGCUGCCUGUGCCGUUUGCUUUGUCUUCAUGGCUGGGGAGGUGGUCGGCGGGUAUCUGGCACACAGCCUGGCCAUCAUGACCGAUGCAGCCCACUUGCUGGCGGAUGUGGGCAGCAUGAUGGGCAGCCUCUUCUCCCUCUGGCUCUCCACCCGUCCAGCCACCCGCACCAUGACCUUUGGCUGGCACCGUUCAGAGACUCUGGGGGCUUUGGCCUCUGUGGUCUCCCUCUGGAUGGUCACUGGCAUCCUCCUGUACCUGGCCUUCGUCCGCCUGCUGCACAGCGACUACCACAUCGAGGGGGGUGCCAUGCUGCUGACCGCCAGCAUCGCAGUCUGUGCCAACCUGUUAAUGGCCUUUGUGCUGCACCAGGCUGGGCCCCCCCACAGCCACGGGUCUAGGGGAGCAGAGUAUGCACCGCUGGAGGAGGGGCCUGAAGAGCCCCUGCCCCUGGGGAACACCAGCGUCCGGGCGGCAUUUGUGCACGUGCUGGGGGACCUCCUGCAGAGCUUUGGGGUACUGGCUGCCUCCAUCCUCAUCUACUUCAAGCCUCAAUACAAGGCAGCCGACCCCAUCAGCACCUUCCUCUUCUCCAUCUGUGCCCUUGGAUCCACCGCUCCCACCCUCCGAGACGUUCUUCGAAUCCUCAUGGAAGGUACCCCCCGCAAUGUGGGGUUCGAACCUGUGCGGGAUACGCUGUUGUCGGUGCCAGGAGUCCGGGCAACCCAUGAGCUGCACCUGUGGGCCCUUACGCUCACUUACCAUGUUGCCUCUGCACACCUGGCCAUCGACUCCACCGCUGACCCUGAAGCCGUCCUGGCUGAAGCCUCAUCCCGGCUCUACUCCCGGUUUGGAUUCUCCAGCUGCACCCUGCAGGUCGAGCAGUAUCAGCCGGAGAUGGCCCAGUGCCUGCGCUGCCAGGAACCCCCCCAAGCCUGAGCCAUGGCCCUGCCCUCACCCCACUGCCAGGCCGAGGCUCAGCCCCAGACUCUCAGCAUCUGCUGCCCUGAUCACAGAGACGGGACCGAGCCAGGUCCAUACCCCUUCCUCUCUCCCUCCUACCACCUGCCAGUUUCCCCAGCCUCAGCCCCAGCCCCAGCCCCAGUGGGCAAGACCAAAGUGUGGCGGGGAGUGGGGUGGGAGUCAGGGGAAUAGAUGUGACUAGUUCAGGGGCGGGGACUCCCAGGCCUCAGUGUGGCAGGGUGUGUUGAAGGCCUGUGGUGCCAUCUCCCCAUGGUUCAUGUGGAGCCACGAACAUCCUUUCCCUGCAGUCCAUUUGUCUGUGUGGCAGGCUGGCUGGCUGGGGGCAUCUGCCUGUCUAUGUGCUGUUGGUGUGCCUAUGCCUGGGGGAGGUCAGUAGGGGCCCCCUCCCCACAUGGCCCUCGCUCUGUCUAUGCAGGGGCCCCAAAGCCCGCACUUUGUCCGUGUGUCUUAGCCCUGUGGUUUUGUCUGUGUGUGUGUGUGUGUGUGUGUGUGUGUGUGUGUGUGUGUUCUUGGUGCUGUGGCCUGUGUGUCUCUGUGCCUAUGUGGCUGUGCUAUGGUUUCUAUGAGUCUGCUCCAUCCAUGUGUCUGUUUGGGGGUCUAUCUCUCCAUCCCUCUGUUGGUGCUGUGCCCUUGGCUAUCCCUGAAAGAGGGAGGACUCCGCUGCAGCUCCACCAAUAAACUUGUGUCUCACUGCAUCUUUCAGCCUGUGUGCUGACUCCUCAGGAGGGGGAAGUCAAAUAGGUCACUUGAGAACAACAGAAUCCCUCCUGUCCCUUCCCAGCCUCUGGAGUGACCUCCCACAGACCUCCUGUCCCUUCCCAGCCCCUCCACCCUCAGAUGGAGGGUAAAAGCCACCAGUCUCUUUACUCCCCUUCCCCUGGCUCACAGCAUGCCUGGGUCCUUGGCUCAGGGACAGUCCCAUGUGCCCUGGGCUUGGUUGCAGGAGAAUGCUGGAAGGUAAGGAGCCAAGGAAUCCCUGGGAGUCAGUCGUUCUCAGAGGUCCCUGCAUGCCAGUGGGCCUCAGGCUGGCUGGAGGGAGGCUGGGUCCCUUUGAGGGAGAAUGGCUAGACCAUAGCACUGAUGUGGGCUUGGUUCUCAGGCCAUCUAAGGUGUCCAGCGGUAGGGACCCCUCAACCCUGAUAGCAGCCAACCCUGAGUCCAGGUUUAGGCUGUGAACACCAAGGACCUCUUUUACACCUAUUCCCCCUUUGUCUUAAGAACUGCAUAUUUUGACACAUUAAGUCUUAAAAUCAGGCUCAUUAAGGGAUUGUUGAUUUUCUCUUUAAAAAAAAUCAAACUCAAGCUGGACAUAGUGGCCUGUGCCUGUAAUCUCAGCCCUUUGGAGGCUGAGGCAGGAGGAUUGUUUGAGCCCAGGAGUUCAAGACCAGCCUGGGCAACCUAGGGAAACCCCUGUCUCUACAAAUAAUUUAAAAAUUAGCUGGGUGUGGUGGUGCAUACCUGUAGUCCCAGCUAUUCAGGAGGCUGAGGCAGGAGGAUUGCCUGAGCCCAGGAGGUCAAGGCAGCAGUCAGCCAUGAUCAUGCCACUGCACUUCAGCCUGGGCAACAGAGCAAGACCUUGUCUC